CAAAGGAGACCCGGUCUCCGAGGCUCAUGGCGAUGCUGGUCCUAGUACCCGGACGAGUUAUGCGGCCUCUGGGUGGCCAACUUUGGCGCUUCUUGCCUCGCGGACUCGAGUUUUGGGGCCCAGCCGAGGGGACUGCGAGAGUCUUGCUGAGGCAGUUCUGCGCGCGGCAAGCGGAGGCGUGGCGUGCCUCGGGGCGCCCUGGCUAUUGCCUGGGAACCCGGCCCCUCAGCACUGCGAGGCCGCCACCCCCGUGGUCGCAGAAGGGCCCCGGAGACUCCACGCGCCCCUCGAAGCCCGGGCCUGUUUCCUGGAAGUCUUUAGCAAUCACAUUUGCUAUUGGAGGAGCUUUACUGGCUGGAAUGAAGCACGUCAAGAAAGAAAAGGCAGAGAAGUUAGAGAAGGAACGGCAGCGACACAUCGGCAAGCCUUUACUUGGGGGACCGUUUUCCCUCACAACUCAUACUGGGGAGCGUAAAACUGACAAGGACUACUUGGGUCAGUGGUUAUUGAUUUAUUUUGGCUUCACUCAUUGCCCUGAUGUCUGUCCAGAAGAACUAGAAAAGAUGAUUCAAGUCGUGGAUGAAAUAGAUAGCAUUACAACUCUGCCAGAUCUAACUCCACUUUUCAUCAGCAUUGACCCAGAGAGGGACACAAAAGAAGCCAUCGCAAAUUAUGUGAAAGAAUUUUCUCCCAAACUGGUUGGCUUGACUGGCACGAGAGAAGAGGUCGAUCAAGUGGCCAGAGCAUACAGAGUGUAUUACAGCCCUGGCCCCAAGGACGAAGAUGAAGACUACAUAGUGGAUCACACAAUAAUAAUGUACUUGAUUGGACCAGAUGGUGAGUUUCUAGAUUAUUUUGGCCAGAACAAGAGGAAGGGAGAAAUAGCUGCUUCAAUUGCCACACACAUGAGGCCAUACAGAAAAAAGAGCUAGCCAAAGCAGUGUUGCUGGAUGCAGUAUUCUCUUGCUAAGAGGAAGGAAACUGUCUCGCAUAGGAGCCUAUAUAAAUAUAAACAUAUAUACGUGCACUCUACAGAAUGGCCUUCAUACCAUGAGAACAUUUCUGUUUUGGAUGGGGAUGUUACCCUUGCGUUCAACCAAAAUUGAUUCUUGGAACUGUAAAGAUUACAACCCAAAGUCUCCCAGGAAGCUGUGGGGAGACCAGAGGAUCAAGCUGAAGUGAAGCCAGUGAAGAGCCCACCUGUGGAAGGACAUGGCGGGGCGAGGCACAGCCAGUGCAUUCCUGCCUGCGAACAGGCCCUCCCAGCAGCUUUGCCGCCUCUCCAUCGUCUUGGGCCCUUGCUCAAAUAGCUGUGGGACUGAAUUUCACAGAAAAGAAUAUAAUUUCCAUAGUGCUCUUGCUUGCCUCUUCUUGAGUUCUUUGCUCUUCUGAGUUCUUGGUGGCUAAUAACAGUCAGAUUAGGGUCUCUGCCAUUCAGAGUUGAUGCUUGAAAACUUUAGUUUUCCUUAUUAAUGAAUAUCACUAUCAGAUUUGACUAAUGAAGAGGAAAUCUAUUGUUUGGGGGAAAAAAAACAUCAGUUUGAUUUCUCUAGGGGUUCUUUUAUGUGAUUUUUAGCUAAGUGGUGUGCCAGGUUUUCAGUGACAUACCAAAUGGAAAUAAGAGGAUAUUGAUCACGAGUGUGAUGCUGAGUACCUUUCUGCAUAUACUGGAUUGUACUUUGUGUAAAGUAAACAUACUCAGUUUUGCUGUUCAGACAAGCGUGAUCUUUUUCAUGGGUGAUGAGUGGGUACAUAGAUGGCUGCACACAGUUCUCAGGAAAGAGACCCACAGGCUCCAGCGGGCAGGUGGGUGGGACGCUUGCUGAAGUGCAGUUCCCCAGACCCAGAGCUGAAUUCACUGAAUCUGCAGUAUGAUGCAGAGACCUGCUUCCAUGACAGAUACCCCAGGUGACUCGGAUGCUGGCGGACUGGGACCAUCCCUUAAGAAAGUGUUUUUUGGGGAAAUAACUUGCCUGGCACAAUGGCUAAUGCCUAUAAUCCCAAAACUUUGGGAGGCCAGGGCCUGAGGAUUGCUAGAGGUUAGGUAUUCAAGACAAGCCUGGGCAACAUAGUGAGACCCCCCCCCCCCGCCCCCAUCUCUACAGAAGAUUUUUUUGGCAUGGUGGCACAUGCCUGUAGUCCUGGCUACUCAGGAGACUGAAAUGGAGUAUCACUUGAGCCCAGGAAUUCAAGGCUUCAGUGAGCUAUAAUCACACCACUGCAUUCCAGCCUGGGCAACAGAGUGAGACCCUCUAGAUAUAUCUAUGUAGAGAUACAGAAAUUAAAAUGAAUUUAAAAAUAAAUAAAUUUGACCCUUCUUUUGGUGUGUCAGCCAUUGAAGAAAAUGAUUAUUGAGUGAUAGAAUGAAUCUUGGCUUUUGUUUCUAAAUUUAACUGCCCUAGAAUCCUGGGUUUGGCCUUUUUCUGCCAGAAGCUGCUGCCCUAGGGGCAAAGUUCUCCAAAAGUUUUUCAGUAAAUCCUAAGAUGCAACAAAUAUAAUGCCUAGAUAGACAACAGAUUCUUUUUACAUGAUAUGUUUCUACACGCACAUGAUAGAGGUCUUUUGGUUUUUAAAUUCUCAAUACUUAAACCUAAAUAUAUCAAAGUAAAAGUAUGUGAAAAAAAACUAUGCUAGUUAUAGGUUGAAUAAUGUCCCCCAAAAUUUAUACAUUGAAGCCCUAAUCUCAGUACUUCAGAAUGUGACUGUAAUUGGAGAUAGGGUCUUUAGAGAGAUAGUUAAAUUAAAAUGAGGCUGCUAGGUUGGCCCUAAUUCUAUAUGACUGGUGUUCUUAAAAUAAUAGAUUAGCUGGGCACAGUGGCUUAUGCCUGUAAUCCCAGCACUUUGGGAGGCCGAGGCGUGCAGAUCACCUAAGGUCAGGAGUUCGAGACCAGCCUGGCCAACAUGGUGAAACGUCGUCUCUCUCCUAAAAAUACAAAAAUUAGCCGGGCAUGGUAGCGGGUGCCUGUAAUCUCAGUUACUCCGGAGGCUGAGGCAGGAGAAUCGCUUGAACCCAGGAGGCAGAGGUGGCAGUGAGGCAAGAUUGCGCCAUCGUACUCCAGCCUGGGCGACAGAGCAAGACUCCGUCUCAAAAAGAAUAGGAGACACAGUGAGACGACCAUGAGAAGCCAGAGAGAAAACAGCCAUCUUACAAGCCAAGAGAGAAGUUGUGAGAAAAAAAAAAAAAAACAAACCCUGCUGACUCCUUGAUUUUUGCCUUCCAAGCUCCAGAACUGUGAGGAAAUAAAUGUCUGUUGUUUUAGCCACCAAACCUGGUAAGGCAGUCCUAGCAAGCUAAUACAAUAGCCUGUUCCUUAAUAAACAACUGCAAGAUUUAGUUUAUAGAAACCAGCUCGGAAGCAGUUGGUUUAGAAUGACUUUCCUAGGAAUCUGGUCAAGAAAGGAACUUACUAAAAGACUAUUCUCAUUUAACAAAAGAGAUAUUAAGUAUCUCAAAGGCCAAAUCUUUAAAAAGAUUAUCUGUUUUAAGCCACAAAACAUUUGUGUGGAUCCCUUUGCAGCAAGUUUGCUCUUAGAUAAGAUUCAGUCUUCGUUCUCAGCUGUUGCAGGUUAAGGCUUGUGAAAUGAUCCAAAAAGGGAACAGCAGCUUUUGGAGAAAACUUUUAUUUGUUCUUCAUUCUAGUGUCAAGUUUAAAGGCUUGAAGUCAGAAUGUUAGAAGUGGGGAAGGGGACCUUAGAGGUGACGUCUUCCAGAUGUUCCUGUUUAUGCACAAGGGGACAGUCUCGGAGAAUUAAGGCGCAAAACUCGGGUCCCAAUUUCUAGGUAGGUUCCUGUUUGUUCUGCUGCUAUCGUGCGCUUAUGGUGACUGUGUGAAUCCAACCAAAACGGAGGUUCCGUAUGCCAGUGGGGCAACGUUUUUCAGCUGCAAAUCUUGGGAAAUCAAAAGCAAGGCUGUUUUUUUUUUCUUUUCUUUUUUGAGACAGAGUUUCACUCUUGUUGCCCAGGCUGGAGUGCAAUGGCGCAAUCUCAGCUCACUGCAACCUCCACCUCCCAGGUUCAAGCAAUUCUCCUGCCUCAGCCUCCCAAGUAGCUGGGAUUACAAGCAUGUGCCACCACACCCGGCUAAUUUUGUAUUUUUAGUAGAGACUGGGUUUCUCUAUGUUGGUCAGACUGGUCUCAAACUCCCGACCUCAGGUGAUCCGCCGCCUCGGCCUCCCAAAGUGCUGGGAUUACAGGUGUGAGCCACCACGCCCGGCCUCAAGGCUGUGUUUCAGUGAAAUAUCCCUUGCAAAUCUUUACCUGGGUGGGUUACAGUGUUUUCACUAGACUCUUCAAUAGAAUUAAUAUUUUAAGAAAUGCCACUUGUUUAUUUGAAAAGUAUAAGAAUCCUAUCAAUGCAGUAGGCAUGAAUGUAUUCAUGUGUCUGGCUGUUCAUGAAGCAGCUGAUAUCUUAAGUGUAAGAGGUGAGAUUUACUGACUACCAGUAAAAUAUGCGAGUUGGGAGGCUAAUGAUUUUAAAUUGUAAAUGCGUCUGCAUAAGAUCCUUUAAAAUAGCUUUUAUUGUUCUUAAAUUUAUGUUUAAAAGAAAUUGACAUUAAUAUUUUCAAAUCAUCCAUAAUCUCCCAAACCUUUUUUGGUUUUCUGUUUAGUACCAUUUAAAUCUUUGUGUAUGUGUAUAUGAGCUACCUUUAAAAGAGCAGUCACCCAUGCGAGCAUUUGUUACCCAAUUAGUUUGUACUUUUUUUUGGUUUUUAUUUUGUUGUUGUUAUUUGUUUCUUUUUGAGAUGGAGUCUCGCUCUUCUCACGCAGGCUGGAAUGCAAUAAUGGCAUAAUCUUGGCUCACUGCAACCUCCGCCUCCCAGGUUCAAGCGAUUCUCCAGCCUGAGUCUCCCGAGUAGCUGGGAUUACAGGCGCCCACCAGCACACCCAGCUAAAUUUUUGUAUUUUUAGUAGAGACGGGUUUCUCCAUGUUGGUCAGGCUGGUCUCGAACUCUCAACCUCAGGUGAUCCGCCCGCCUUGGCCUCCCAAAGUGCUGGGAUUACACGCGUGAGCCACUGCGCCCGGCCUAGUUUGUGCUUUUUACUUACCAGUUAGGGGUUAUAUUACUGUGUAACAAAAUGGACGGUUAUUUCUAUUCAUUAACAAGAUUCAAGUAAUAGCCUCUUUAGCCACAUAUUCCUUAAUAACACCUUUAGACCUUAUAGGGGUAAUUAUUUUCUAUAUACUUUUCCAAUGUAUUUGAAAGUUUGUUGGCUCUUCUUCCGUAAUUAUACUAUAUCCUCAGUAAAGAAAGUUUGGCAUACAGAAAAGUUGAAGGAAGAAAAUUUUCAAUCACUGUUGUUCCACUACCAAGAAAUAAUACUUGGAGGUAUUUCCUUUCAAUCUUCAACAUGAGGAUGCUAAUGUCCCCCUCAUAAGGGGCCUUAAAGUCACUGACUCUGUGCACUAUUUCAUGAGAACAUUGAUGUGGGUAUUUAACCGAAAGAAAACUUGAGUUUUCUUUUUUUCCUUUUUAUUGUGAAAAUUUGGAAACUUAUUCAAAAAGUAGAAUAGUUAACUAAUUGAUGUACCCAUCAGCAAGCUUCAGUGAUUACCACCAUUUAAUUUUGUCUGCACCCCCCCACCCACUGCCACCCCAGCCCAUUCCCAGCAUGUGCCUCUGAAAGAGACCAACUUUGUCCUUUAAAAACAACCACAGUUGGCUGGGCACGGUGGCUCAUGCCUGUAAUCCCAGUACUUUGGGAAGCAAAGGCGGGUGGAUCACCUGAGGUUGAGAGUUCGAGACUGGCCUGACCAACAUGGAGAAACCCGUCUCUACUAAAAAUACCAAAGUUAGCCGGGCGUGGUGGCGGGUGCCUGUAAUCCCAGCUACUCGGGAGGCUGAGGUAGGAGAAUCGUGUGAAUCUGGGAGGCGGAGGUUGCAGUGAGCCGAGAUCACGCCACUGCACUCCAGCCUGGGCAACAAGAGUUGUCUCAAAAAACAAAAAAGAAAGAAAGAAAAAAACAACCACAGUUUCAUCAGCACAGCAAAAAGGUUUUUGUUUUUGCUCUUGGAUUUUGUCGUUUGGUUUUUGCUUAAUAUCAAAUAUCCAGUCAGUGUAAACUCGUUUAUAAUUUGGUCCUUUGAUUUCAAGGAGCUAUGAUGCAGUUCGUUGUGGGGAUGUGUUGUCUCCAUGUCAUACAUGUGACUUUGUCCAUGUUUGCACCCAGUUCAAGGAAGACACAACCCUAGGGAAAGACAACCCUCCCCGCCAAGCCUCUCUUCCCAUUCUUAAACAUAGGGUGGCGUUAUUCAGGUUGGACCAGUUUAAAAAGACUAACGCAUUUGUCCUCGUUGUUGGGUGUUUUUUUUCUUUAAAUUUGUAAAACAGGAAUAAUUGUGUUAGGAUGAAGUAUGAUACUAGGAGAACAGGGAAAACUAACCCAUCGUGUUAAAAGUCAGAAUAGUGCUUAACUCUGGCAGGAGGUGAGAUGGUUAGUAAUUCAGAAGGGGGUGCCAGGAGAGCUUCCAGAGCCAUUGAAAUGUUCAGUAGCUUGAUCUGGGUGAUGAUUUACAUACAUAAAAACAUAUUAAACUUUGAACUUAAGAUUUAUGCCUUUUACUGUUUGCACCCUAUAACUCCAAAAGAAAAGUAGAGGGGAAAAAGAGUCCCUGCAAAAGGCAGUCUUGAAAGAAAGCAAGUCUGUGAUGUGGAGAAUGCAUUGGACAGCUCUCAGCAAUUUGCUGUAGCUUGGGCAGAGAGAUAAAAGCUAAUGCCAGCAUCAGGUUGCCCAGGCGAGAGAAGGCCUGAAAGAAGACAGCGUGGAGAAAGUGUCAGCAAGCUUCAGCAACAGCAGGAGGCAGAUGGUAGGAGAGUGGGCCUCAGGUGUGGUGUGGCAGAGCAGAGUAGCCACACUUAGGCCCCAGAGACAGUGUCUUCUCACCCUCAGUUGAAGGGGCAGGAAAUCAAUCGCUCUAGUCACCCCUAAGCUGGAGGACGGACCUAAAGUUGCCACAGCUUUGAGAGGCAAAGAAGUUUGCUCAGUGGCUUUUAGAGACUUCUAGGGCCCUGGGACCCUGACACUGAGGAGGAGCAAACUGAAGGGGAGAGUGGGCACAUUCCUUGUUGGCUGCUGUGGUGAGCAGCAGCUGGUCGUUGUCAGUCAAGCUCCGGACCACUCUGAUGAUGCUCACUGCAUUUUGAUGGAGUAAGCCAGGGACAUUACCACUGUGUUUGAGCCAUCUGAAGUAUUCCUGGGUGGGUCUGCAGUUGGCAGCCCGUGAUCCUUUUUCCAUUCAAGGAUGAUGCAAAGGUAAGGGGCCAAGGCUGAGCUCUGUAGAUGCCUGUGAGAGCCUCCUGGUCUCAAGAGGUCAUACCAAGGGCCUUGGCCACCAAGGUUUCGUGAGGACCUUGAGGUGGUUUCGCCAUCACAAUGUCAGACGUGUCACACACCAUCUGGUAUGUCCUCACUGUAUAGAGGAAGAAGGGCCCAAGUGGUGAAUUAUCUACAAGUUUGUAGCAAAGCUAAUACUCAGACUCCCUCUACAGCCUUGCUACUCAGUGUAGUCUGUGGUCCGGCAGUGUCACACCACUGGGGUACUUAGCAGAAAUGCAGCUUCUCAGGCUCCACUCCAGCUCUCCUCAAUCACAGUCUGUUUUUUUGUUUGUUUGUUUGUUUGUUUUGAGAUGGAGUUUCGCUCUUGUUGCCUAGGCUGGAGAGCAGUGGUGCGAUCUUGGCUCACUGCAACCUCCACCUCCCUGGUUCAAGUGAUUCUGCUGCCUCAGCCUCCCAAGUAGCUGGGAUUACAGGCGCCCGCCACCAUGCCCGGUGGCGUGCAUGGUAAUUUUUGUAUUUUUAGUAGAAACAGGAUCUCGCCAUGUUGGCCAGGCUGGUCUUGAACUCCUGACCUCAGGUGAUCCACCCGCCUUGGCCUCCCAAAGUACUGGGGAUUACAGAUGUGAGCCACCACGCCUGGCCCACAGUCUGUAUUUUAACAAGAUCCCCACCUCAGUCUUAGGCACAUGGAUUCUCCUCAACCCCCAAUACCACAGAGUCUAUUAAUUUUUACCCAAUAGGGAAGGGGAAAAAGUCAAGAAAGAAUAAUGAAUUAAGUAAUCUUUCCCCCUCCAGGAAGCUCUUUAUUUAAUUUCGCUCCCAUGAAACACAAUUUGAAGAGUCUCUCAAAUAAACAAAUUCCAUUUUCUGAUAAUUAUUUAAUUGCCCCACUUUUGAAAUUUUUGUCAAAGACGACUGUCACUCCCUGUCAGAACUUCUAUUCAGCACAGUAUACCAAGCGUUUCUCCAUCGAGUUGUUAUAAUAUGAUCAAAAAGCAGGGAGAGAUGCUGCUUGGUUACCCUGUGGGGCCUUAUCGGGGCUCAGUGCAGUCUUUCCAUGUAGGCAUUCUCAAAUACUCAAUUGAAACCUGAUUGAGGAUCAUUUGAUCUCUGUUGGCCCUAGUGCAGUAGGCUGCUGAGAACCACUGAUGCAAUAGACUGAGAGACUAACUGCCUGCUUCCCUGUCAGCCCAGGCUCUGCUAAGGCCGUCUUAGUUACAGAAGAAAGUGGGGCAGAGAGCCCUGCAAGGAUUACAUUCCAUUCCUAACGGAGACAGGCAAGCGUUCAGUGCCCGAAGCAGGGCAGGCCUUUGUAUGGCUCACUUUUCCCUGUACCAGCCUCAGCCCCGUACAUUCAGAAAGCCCUGUCGGGAACGUGCGGGAUCACAGCACAAGACAGUCAUUCACUGAUUGAUUGACGACGUCAACAUUGCGGAAUACCUAUGUUAAGCUGAGUACGAGGGAUAUAAAAAGUAGGCCCUGGAGAGUGCCUCUGGGAUGCACAUAACCAGACAAGAUAAAGAAAAGGCAGAUCACGAGAUCAAGAGAUCGAGAUCAUCCUGGCCAACAUGGUGAAACCCCAUCUCUACUAAAAUUACAAAAAUCAGCUAGACGUGGUGGCGGGCGCCUGUAGUCCCAGCUACUCAGGAGGCUGAGGCAGGAGAAUCGCUUGAACCCGGGAGGCAGAGAUUGCACUGAGCUGAGGUCAUGCCACUGCACUCCAGCCUGGCAACAGGGCAAGACUCCAUCUCAAAAAAAAAAAAAAAGAAAAAAAAGAAAAAUUAGGGCAGCUUUUAGACAUGAGGCCCCAAAGUGCCAACUAGUGCACCUAAACUUCAACUCUCUUUUGAGUGUUUUAUGUAUCUACUCAGCAUCCAGUUGUAAAUAUGCAAAAAUCAAUGCCUACUGUAUUUAAAAAUUACUAAAUUCACAAUAACCACACAGAAUCUAUAAUAAAUAGAAUCAAUGUAAUAAUGACUCAGAUCCAGGGGAAGAAAAUUAUAAAAUUUUGGAAAAAAUGAUGAGCUAUUAAUUAAGAAAAUAGUUUGUUCCUUGGUGAGAAGACUCAAUGUAAAUAUGUCAGUUUUCUCCUGACUUAAGUCUUCAACACAGGCCUAAUAAUAUUGCAGUGGCAAAUGAUUGCCAGGGGCAGGAGGGGAUUUGGGGAAGUGGUAAAAAUGAUCUGUGUCUUGGUAGUGGUCGCUGCACAACUGCAUACAUCUGUGAAAACUCACUGAACUGCGCACUUUAAAAGGGUGAAUUGUAAUAUACAUACCUCAAUAAACCUUACUUAAAAAUUA